ACAUAGCUAGUAAGUUCUAGCUAGCACUGAGUGCUGUGCCCGUGAAAUUUAUCUACAUAGGCUUUCACUUAACCUGCAGACAGAACUCAGUUAGUCGGGGACAAUUUCCCUCAAUGUUAACAGCACUGUUCCACCGCAACGUGGAACAACAGCUUUAAAACGUGCUCUUCGUAGGCCCGGCUACUCCAAGAACAGUGCCUCCCGCCAGACCCAGGCGGCUUCCUUCACCCGCAACCCGAGAGACGACCCGCCGGGCCCGCCCCGCGGAAGCCGCCGGUUGCCAGGCCAAGGAGUGGACUAGGGUCGCCGGGGAAGCGGUUUGGGAGAGCCCAUGGUGACUGCGUGAGUGGAGCCCAGCUGUGUGGAUGCCCCAGCAUGGAUGACUACAUGGUCCUGAGAAUGAUUGGGGAGGGCUCCUUCGGCAGAGCUCUUUUGGUUCAGCAUGAAAGCAGUAAUCAGAUGUUUGCCAUGAAAGAAAUAAGGCUUCCCAAGUCUUUCUCUAAUACACAGAAUUCUAGGAAGGAGGCUGUUCUUUUAGCCAAAAUGAAACACCCUAAUAUUGUUGCCUUCAAAGAAUCAUUUGAAGAGCUUAUAUCUGUUUUAGCUGAAGGACACUUGUAUAUUGUGAUGGAAUACUGUGAUGGAGGGGAUCUAAUGCAAAAGAUUAAACAGCAGAAAGGAAAGUUAUUUCCUGAAGACAUGAUACUUAAUUGGUUUACCCAAAUGUGCCUUGGAGUAAAUCACAUUCACAAGAAACGUGUGCUACACAGAGAUAUCAAGUCCAAGAAUAUCUUCCUCACUCAGAAUGGAAAAGUGAAAUUGGGAGACUUUGGAUCUGCCCGUCUUCUCUCCAAUCCGAUGGCAUUUGCUUGUACCUAUGUGGGAACUCCUUAUUAUGUGCCUCCAGAAAUUUGGGAAAACCUGCCUUAUAACAAUAAAAGUGACAUCUGGUCCUUGGGUUGCAUCCUGUAUGAACUCUGUACCCUUAAGCAUCCAUUUCAGGCAAAUAGUUGGAAAAAUCUUAUCCUCAAAGUAUGUCAAGGGUGCAUCAGUCCACUGCCGUCUCAUUACUCCUAUGAACUUCAGUUCCUAGUCAAGCAGAUGUUUAAAAGGAAUCCCUCACAUCGCCCCUCGGCUACAACGCUUCUCUCUCGAGGCAUCGUAGCUCGGCUUGUCCAGAAGUGCUUACCCCCCGAGAUCAUCAUGGAAUAUGGUGAGGAAGUAUUAGAAGAAAUAAAAAAUUCGAAGCAUAACACACCAAGAAAAAAAACAAACCCCAGCAGAAUCAGGAUAGCUUUGGGAAAUGAAGCAAGCACAGUGCAAGAGGAAGAACAAGAUAGAAAGGGUAGCCAUACUGAUUUGGAAAGCAUUAAUGAAAAUUUAGUUGAAAGUGCAUUGAGAAGAGUAAACAGAGAAGAAAAAGGUAAUAAGUCAGUCCAUCUGAGGAAAGCCAGUUCACCAAAUCUUCAUAGACGACAGUGGGAGAAAAAUGUACCCAAUACAGCUCUUACAGCUUUGGAAAAUGCAUCCAUACUCACCUCCAGUUUAACAGCAGAGGACGAUAGAGGUGGUUCUGUAAUAAAGUACAGCAAAAAUACUACUCGUAAGCAGUGGCUCAAAGAGACCCCUGACACUUUGUUGAACAUCCUUAAGAAUGCUGAUCUCAGCUUGGCUUUUCAAACAUACACAAUAUAUAGACCAGGUUCAGAAGGGUUCUUGAAAGGCCCCCUGUCUGAAGAAACAGAAGCAUCGGACAGUGUUGAUGGAGGUCACGAUUCUGUCAUUUUGGAUCCAGAGCGACUUGAGCCUGGGCUAGAUGAGGAGGACACGGACUUUGAGGAGGAAGAUGACAACCCCGACUGGGUGUCAGAGCUGAAGAAGCGAGCUGGAUGGCAAGGCCUGUGCGACAGAUAAUGCCUGAGGAAAUGUUCCUGAGUCACGCUGAGGAGAGGCUUCACUCAGGAGUUCAUGCUGAGAUGAUCAUGAGUUCAUGCGACGUAUAUUUUCCUUUGGAAACAGAAUGAAGCAGAGGAAACUCUUAAUACUUAAAAUCGUUCUUGAUUAGUAUCGUGAGUUUGAAAAGUCUAGAACUCCUGUAAGUUUUUGAACUCAAGGGAGAAGGUAUAGUGGAAUGAGUGUGAGCAUCGGGCUUUGCAGUCCCAUAGAACAGAAAUGGGAUGCUAGCGUGCCACUACCUACUUGUGUGAUUGUGGGAAAUUACUUAACCUCUUCAAGCCCCAAUUUCCUCAACCAUAAAAUGAAGAUAAUAAUGCCUACCUCAGAGGGAUGCUGACCACAGACCUUUAUAGCAGCCCGUAUGAUAUUAUUCACAUUAUGAUAUGUGUUUAUUAUUAUGUGACUCUUUUUACAUUUCCUAAAGGUUUGAGAAUUAAAUAUAUUUAAUUAUGA